AGAGUAGGAGAUUUCAAGAUGCAUCUCAAGUCUUUCUCCUGUGGUCUAUCCUGCUGGGAGGCAGUCUAGUGCAUGGGAGCUAAAAGGCAGGACUUGCUUUGUGAGCCUCUUCAGGUCAGCGUGAGUCUGUUCAGUUGCAACAGGAACAAGAGAAAAAGAAUCCAUAUCAUCCACCUUUUAAAGAAGUUAGGCAUCUACUGGCAAGGUGGAAGAAAUCAACAAAUCUAUCAGGGAUAUACCUCUCAGAAUGGGGCAGACCAACGUAACCUCCUGGAGGGAUUUUGUCUUCCUGGGCUUCUCCAGUUCUGGGGAGUUGCAGCUCCUUCUCUUUGCCUUGUUCCUCUCUCUGUAUCUAGUCACUCUGACCAGCAAUGUCUUCAUUAUCAUAGCCAUCAGGCUGGAUAGCCAUCUGCACACCCCCAUGUACCUCUUCCUUUCCUUCCUAUCCUUCUCUGAGACCUGCUACACUUUGGGCAUCAUCCCUAGAAUGCUCUCUGGCCUGGCUGGGGGGGACCAGGCUAUCUCCUAUGUGGGCUGUGCUGCCCAGAUGUUCUUUUCUGCCUCAUGGGCCUGUACUAACUGCUUCCUUCUGGCUGCCAUGGGCUUUGACAGAUAUGUGGCCAUCUGUGCUCCACUCCACUAUGCCAGCCACAUGAAUCCUACCCUCUGUGCCCAGCUGGUCAUUACUUCCUUCCUGACUGGAUACCUCUUUGGACUGGGAAUGACACUAGUUAUUUUCCACCUCUCAUUCUGCAGCUCCCAUGAAAUCCAGCACUUUUUUUGUGACACGCCACCUGUGCUGAGCCUAGCCUGUGGAGAUACAGGCCCGAGUGAGCUGAGGAUCUUUAUCCUCAGUCUUUUGGUCCUCUUGGUCUCCUUCUUCUUCAUCACCAUCUCCUACGCCUACAUCUUGGCAGCAAUACUGAGGAUCCCCUCUGCUGAGGGGCAGAAGAAGGCCUUCUCCACUUGUGCCUCGCACCUUACAGUGGUCAUUAUUCAUUAUGGCUGUGCUUCCUUCGUGUACCUGAGGCCCAAAGCCAGCUACUCUCUUGAGAGAGAUCAGCUUAUUGCCAUGACCUAUACUGUAGUGACCCCCCUCCUUAAUCCCAUUGUUUAUAGUCUAAGGAAUAGGGCUAUACAGACAGCUCUGAGGAAUGCUUUCAGAGGGAGAUUGCUGGGUAAAGGAUGAAGGUUACCCCAAUAGGACACUUUCUUCUGUGUAGGCUGGGCAUAGACCAAGAACCCAAGCCAAAGGGCCAGGUAUUCAAGGCCUCAGGCCAAAGCUGUCCUACCCCCAAUCUUCUGGGAAAGCCUUAUCCUGCCUCUUGCCCUUCCCCCUGACUGCUUGGAAUGCAGAGGCGGGGCUUCCUGCUCUGCUCACUGUGCACAACUCAAAAUGAGCCCAAAAUCUGAAUUUUAACUUUCAGCCUCCUAGAUGCCACCCCUAGUUACUGAAACCCAUUGAGAAUUAAAAAUUUAAUUAAGAUAAUCAAGAAUUUUUUAAUUGAGCUGAACAAAAUGAGGGAAGUUUGGAGUGUUCAAGUUCAAGGCAGGGCUGGCUGGAGCCCAUCAGGGAUACUGUAGAGAUUUCUAAAAUCAUUACAUAAUUAGACUAUUUGACCUGUAAUGUUCUUCCAAGAUUUGAAACCUGGGGAAUAUCAGCUUGACAGGUUAGUUUAAAGCUUUGUUAAAUGAACAGGUGGGUCAUUUUUACUCCCACUGGGUGUCUUUCAUCUUUUUAUGUUUUUAUUUUUUUUAAUUUCAACUAUUAUUUCAUAUACAGUGGGGCACAUGUGCUUAUACAUUCCUCAUUGUGCUAUUGACAGUAGCAAAAACAUGGAAUCAUCUUUUUAUAUAGUUGUCCUCACUAUCUCUGACUCUGUUACUUUGCCCUUUUUGUUUUGAUUGAUUUUCCAAGCUGGGUGCACUCUAUUUCAGAAAAUAUAUUUACUUCCUAUUUUUUUUUAUAACUGUUAAUGUUCCCUGGUAGCUUCAGAAUCUUGAGUGUCAAAGACCUUUCUCAUUUGGGUCGCUUAUCAAAUUGGAUACUGUUCUUUUGAAUCUAUUGCAGAACUAUCUAUUCUGCCUAUUCCACUUUCCACAUAUAAUGUGGUUAUAUAUAGCGGCGGACAUUAUUAGAGAAAGUGUAAUGAACUCACAAGACCGUCAGGCAGGAGUUUGAAUCCAAACUCUUCAACUUACUAGCUGUGUGACUCUAGGUAAGUUAUUUAACAUUUUUUUCAGCUUCCGAGUCUUAUCUUUACAAUGGUUGGUGACUAAACAGGAUCAUGCAUACAAAGAAUUUAGCACAACCCUUGGAUCAUAGCGAUCGUCCAAUAAAUUCCAGUUGCUACUAUUAAAAUGUGUGAAGGAAAAAGAUAUUGGCUUUUAGUUUAGGUAGAGUUUACUCUAGGUGGAGGAUCAGAGAAGACUUCAUGUCUUAAAUAGUAUCUGAACUUGUUCCUAAAGGAUGGGUGAGCUUUGAAUGCACUGACUGGGGAGAAAGUACAUUCUCAGAAGAGAGAAUGUAAUAGCCAAAGGCUUGAUGGUAAGACAAUAUAAGCCUAGUUUAAUGUGUGUGAGUUAUUCAGAGGGGCUGGAAACAACUCACAAAUGAUGCUGAGAAGUUAGUUUGAGUCAUGACUUACUUGUUGAAAUAAUUUGAAUACCUUGCUUCAGACAUGGUCCUUUUGUCUAUAGGAGAUAAGGCACAGUAAAACGUUGAACAGAGAGAGGCAUCUGGGAAGGGAUUCAGGAAGAUUAAUCCAGCAGCAAAGGGGAUGAUAGAUUUCAGUAGAGAGAAACCAGAGGCAAGGAGAUCAGCAAGAAACCCAUGGAUAUCAGCUUAAAAAAAGGCAAAGAGGCUUGAAUAUGGAUAGUGACAUUCAGAGACUGAAGGAAAUCACAAACAUGAGAUUUUGAGAAGGUAGAAUUCACAGGAUUUGGCAGUGAGAUAGAAGUGGGGCAUGGCUUGAGAGACAAGGAAAGACCUUAGGCCGAGAAGAUAUUUUUCAGACAGAAAUCCAUAUUUUUUCAUGCUUUCAGGAAAGAAAUACAUCCUCUAAUUGGAAUUUGAUGAAAACAAUUUGAGAGGAAGGAAGCUAGAGCUCAGAGAAGAGAACAGGAUGAAGACAAGUAGAUGAGUUAGUCAGAUAGCCAAAAGGGCCUCAUCAGGGGAGAAAGGCCAUCUACUCUGAAGUUCUCAAUAUUGGAAGAAGUAAUGCCUCAUUGCACUGAGGCCAUGUGAGCAAAUUCAUUUCACCAGUUCAUUCAGUCUGCCCAGCAUAACAUUGACUAAAUGCACAGUGACGAAUGGUUAGUAAGGAUGUUUCAAGUAUUGCUAAGUAAUACUUAGAGGUCUAACUUCCACAUGUAGUAGUCUUAAGUAUGGAAGGGUAUAAAAUCACUUGGAGGGAUUUUUCCAAAUAGGUGUUUUUGGAAUCUAUCUAAUUUGUUUCUACCUUGAAACAAUUGAUUUGGGAUAGGGACAACAUAAUAGUCUUCAAAAUCUCGUUUGGUGAUUCAAAUUUCCUCUCUUGAUUAAGUAUGUGACUACGCGCUUAGAAAGGGCAAACUCUUCUUCCAGGUACACACAUUUGACCCACUAAAUGACUAAUAAUUUGAUUUAGGCCUUGAAAAUUUUUGGCAGGGUUAGCAUUGGGGGAAUGGAAUCACAUCCACCUUUGCUUGUGAUUAUUUUCAGCACAAAUAGUUUUAGACUAUCCAUAUGUGGUAAGUGUGAUAUUAAACAAUGCUAAUUUUCGAUGGCCUAUAUCUUUUCUAACUGUACUAUUUUUGGUAACUUAUAAUCAGGCAAUUUAGACAUUUGUGAACAUUAAUUUUGAAAAUACUUUCUGCUUGUUAUAUUCCAUAGUAUUUGACUAUUUAAGAAAAGAAUCACUAAAAUACCUGUAUGUUGUUAGUAUCAAUGAUAACUUUUUAGCUUUAACCAACUUUUUGUUUAAAAAAGGCUCCUAUGACAGGAUUUGUCCUGCACAGAUUCAUUUCUAUGCAGAGGAAGGGACUGAGACUUAAGAUGGUAAUCAAGUGGCAACAUGAAUGGAUUGGUAAGUGGGGACUAUUUGUGCAGAACGCUAGCAGUUUUAUACACAGCAAUUAAGAUAUCUAAGAAUUCUCACCAGCAAAUGACACCAUUACCUUUUAUAGAUCAAAUCAGAAUGUCGGCAUAUAAACCUGUUCAGAAUAAACCUGGCCUGAAAAUUUUUGAAGAUAGCAUCACCUCUUCUUUUUUUAAAAUUAAUUCUUAAUUUUAUAAAUAAUUCUAUUAACUGUUACUUUAACAGGAUAUUGAAGUAUUAUUUUUAUUACAUUAAAACUUAAGAGAAAAUACGGGAGCUUGGAGGACAAGAGAAAGCCCUGCUAUGCUGGAAUUUUGUCUUUCUGAGAGUAAUAACAUCUACAAUAAUUUUGAAGUAUGGAAAAAAAACAAGAAGAAAACAGGUGUUAUGCUGAUCUGUGUGUUGUUUCAUUGUACAAACUAAAAUAUUCAUGUUCCCCAGAAAAUCAAAUAUCUUUAUUUUCAAAUUUAAAUUUAAACACAUUCCAAAGUUUAAAAAAAUUGUUUGAAAAUUGCCUUGGAUUUUAUUUAUCUACUAUACCAUGGCCCUUCUUUACAGUAAAAUUAGCUGCCCACUCUUAUAUGAGUACAGUUCCCAGAAAUAUAGAAGCUCAACAUUUUACUUAACUUUGCCCCAAAAAAUAUUUUUAAAAAGAAUUACUUUAUUCUAUAAUCGGAAUAAAGCAAAAUGAUAAAGACGUGCAAAACAGAACAAAUAAAAAUAGAAACUUUGACACCCCUCAGCAGUGACUAGUUGCAUACAAAAUAGCUUCCACUCCUCCAACUCUAUUAACCUUUCUAUCUCCCACCCUUGAGAUUUUUUAAGAUCCUACAAUAAAUGUAAUAUGCACACAAACACAAGCACACACACACACACACACACACACACACACACACGAGGCCAUCUUUAUCUUCCACAUUUGCCUGUACUCUUUGCCCCCCAGUAAAUUUCCCACGACACUAAGAUUUUCUACGAUCCACGAGGAGCUGCUUAUUAGUUGCCAAAGUAGGAAUUGGUGAAGCCAACGUAGUCAUAGCCAGAGAGAUGGCUUCGACCCCGUGGGUCCAUAUAUUGCUGCAUAUGUGUGGCACAGAAUGACACUUGCUCUGGGGUAAGGGCCUGAAAAGUAUAAAAAGAGAAAAAUACAGUUAUAGGGAUUCAAAAUAGCUGGUUCCUUGGGGCUUCCCAUAUUACGCCAUAAAUGCAGGAGAUGGAGAGUCUCUGGAAGACGCAAGCCCUAUUUCUAUUACACACAAUUUUUAUCUCAUAAAUUUAUAAUUUCUAAUGAGUAACUUAACUUUUAAUCUCAGCCCUUUCUUGAAAAAGAGAGCUUACUCACUUUGAUUAUUCUGUAAAUCUCAUUCCCUAAAGUUGUUUUAUUAAAUAGAAGGAAUUAUAUGCCUAACAACAUUUGUUGACCACUUGAUCUAUUUCAUCUUCCUGGCUGCUUUGAGAUGUGGGGACUAGCAUGUUUUAUGAGUAAGGUAAAAUACUCAAGAAGGUAGAAUAACUCACCAGUGGUUACACUGCCAGAAAGUGGUAGAGCUGGGACUUGAACCUAUGAUCCUCUUAUGCCAAAGAGUUCCUCUAUUCACUGUGCUGUUUGAUUACCAAGUGGAUCCCUAAAGACUCCAAUAAGUUAGCGUGUGGGUGGGUGGCUCCAGAUAGUGUCUGGAAGACCACAUCAUUUUCUUUUUGUAACAGCUUUGUCGAGGUAUGAUUGAUAAAGAAUUGCACCUUUAAUGUGUACAGUUUGAUGAGUUUAGACAAUUGGAUGAGUUUGUGCAAAACGAUACCAUCAUGUAUGUGACCCUUUGUAAUCUGGUUUCUGCUUAAUUGUUUUCCCUUUCACUUUCUGUUACUAUCUUCUUACCUUAUGCUUUAGGUAUUAGGAAAAUCUGUUUUCUCAAGUUCCUUUGCACACACACUUGCCUUUGCCUGAAACACUUAGGCUUUCCUUUGAUGACUUGAUGAGUUCCUGCACGUCCUUCAACACUCACCCUGUGUUAAUCAUAGAUGAUACUUUCCCUGAUGCAAGUAUUUUAAGGAGAGGAAUGAAGAAAGCUCUUGGAAUCAGAGAGAAGAGAGAUUACUUCUGGUUGUAAUAAAAUUCCCCACAUCUUUGUUCCCAUGACAGAUGUGUUUGCUUCUGUUACAGUGUUUUUAACUUGUAAAGUUCUGUCUUCCCCACUACACCUGAAUUUAGGGACUGUGUCUUACUAAAGUUUGCACUCCUCAUGCCUG